AUAUCACCUGAGAGAGUUCCCAAGUCUACAAUUGCUCUACUAGUUACUAUUCAGUGUUUGUGAAAAAUUUUAAUCUCAGUACUGUGAAGAAGCUGGAAAAAGGGAUAUUAUGGGGCUAAAAGCUCUCUGUUUGGGGCUGCUUUGUGUUCUUUUUGUCUCUCAUUUUUACACACCCAUGCCAGACAACAUUGAAGAAAGCUGGAAAAUAAUGGCCUUGGAUGCCAUCGCUAAAACUUGUACAUUUACGGCUAUGUGUUUUGAAAAUAUGCGUAUUAUGAGAUAUGAAGAGUUUAUAUCCAUGAUAUUCAGGCUGGAUUAUACCCAACCACUUUCAGAUGAAUACAUCACAGUGACUGAUACAACAUUUGUUGACAUUCCAGUACGAUUGUACUUGCCAAAAAGAAAGUCAGAAACCCGAAGGCGAGCUGUGAUAUAUUUUCAUGGUGGUGGUUUUUGUUUUGGAAGUUCCAAACAGAGGGCUUUUGACUUCCUGAAUAGAUGGACGGCAAACACGCUUGAUGCUGUUGUUGUAGGCGUGGACUAUAGGCUGGCUCCUCAACACCACUUUCCUGCUCAGUUUGAAGAUGGCCUUGCUGCAGUCAAAUUUUUUCUUUUGGAAAAAAUUCUUACAAAAUAUGGAGUGGAUCCCACCCGAAUCUGCAUUGCGGGAGACAGUUCUGGGGGCAAUUUAGCAACAGCGGUCACUCAACAGGUGCAGAAUGAUGCUGAAAUAAAACAUAAAAUCAAGAUGCAAGUCUUACUUUACCCUGGCUUACAGAUAACAGAUUCUUAUUUGCCAUCUCACCGAGAAAAUGAGCAUGGUAUAGUUUUGACCAGGGAUGUAGCCAUAAAACUCGUGAGCUUAUAUUUCACCAAGGAUGAAGCACUUCCCUGGGCAAUGAGAAGAAACCAACACAUGCCUCUGGAGUCAAGACAUCUGUUUAAGUUUGUUAACUGGAGUAUUCUUCUUCCUGAGAAGUAUAGAAAAGACUAUGUAUAUACUGAACCAAUUCUUGGAGGACUUAGUUAUUCAUUGCCAGGACUUACAGACAGCAGAGCAUUACCCUUGUUGGCCAAUGAUUCUCAGUUACAGAAUUUGCCACUAACCUAUAUUCUUACUUGUCAACAUGAUCUCUUAAGAGAUGAUGGACUUAUGUAUGUUACAAGACUUCGAAAUGUUGGAGUCCAAGUUGUUCAUGAACAUAUUGAGGAUGGAAUUCAUGGAGCUUUAUCAUUCAUGACUUCACCAUUUUAUUUACGUCUAGGUCUUAGGAUAAGAGAUAUGUAUGUAAGUUGGCUGGAUAAGAAUUUAUAAAUAUGUGAUGUGUAUGUAUAGCCCUUACAUAGUGGAUUGUAAUUUGUGAUAUUUUGUGGUUUUGGAGCAAAGAACAAUGUCAUUUGAGUUAUCUAAAUCUACAUUUGCAACAUUUGUAGCAGUUAAUGUGUGUCCUUGAAGAGUUAUUAAAUUUUCUGACUUGCAGACCCUGAAUAUGUAAAAUGUAUGUAAUCCUGCCUAUUUUCUCCUUACUUAUAAUUUAUUAUAAUUAUGUUGGUUCUAAUAAGAACCAAUGCUUAUUAAAGUUGAGAAAUAAGAGUGGUUAUUGGCAAAUUAAGCAAGAUACUUUCCAGAUAGGCACAGAAAUUGUUGUAGUGAGUGGGAAGAGGAAAAAACAUGGAACAAACUUGCUGCUAAAAAUAUAUGGAAACCACUGGACUAAAUAAACCCUAAGGACCCUAUAUUAGUUUCCUGUGACUAUUGUAGCAAAUUACUACAAAUUCAGUCGCUUUAAACAACAGAUAUUUAUUCUUUUACAGUUCUGGGGUCCUAAAGCAUGAAAUUAGUAUUAACUAGGCCCAAACCAAGUCACAGGCAAGAGACAUGACUCCCUUGGAGACUCUCUAGAAGGUGCUCUUUGCCUCUUUUAACCUCUGGUGGCUGCCAGUAUUCUUUGACUAUUCUUAGAUCAGUUUAAUCUUGAAGGCCAGCAUCUUCCAAUCUCUUUCUGCUUCAUCUUCACAUUGCCUUCUUCUCUGCCUGUGUCUAAUCUCCCUAUGGGCUUCUCUUAGAAAAACACAUGUGUUUACAUUUAGGAGGGUCCACCUGAAUAGUCUAGGAUAAUCUCUGCAUCUCACGAUCCUCAAUUUAAUUGUAUUUGCAGAUUUCCCCACCCUUUUCUAUAUAAAGUAACCUUCAGAGAUUAGGAUGUAGUUAUCUUUUGGGAGGCCAUUUUUAAAAAUAUUUUUUAAAGGAGGCAGCAGAUCAAUAUUAUAAUUCAAGAAUCUGAUCUAAAUAUGCAUUCAAUAAUGAAGAACAUUUGAGUAUGGACUAGAAAAGCUUCUCCAAAAAACUUUCAAAUAUAUCAUCUCAAAUUACCUAAAGAAUAAAUCACUUCUGUAGCCCUUUUGUUGAGUGGAAUCAUAAACAAAAAACUGAAAAUUUAUUGCUAUGAAAACAGAUCCAUGGUACAAUGUUAUAAAUUUUGAGUAUUAAGCAUAGUCAGUUGAAUCCAACUAAGAAGUUAAAAAUGUAGUAAGAAAUGUGUAUAUGUAUGAGUAUGUGCAUGUGUGUGGGAAAAAUCUACCAUCCAAUUGACCCAAAAACAACUUACUCAGUUGGGACCAGACAUUUUUCUCAAUUCUCCAUGAUUCAGAAGGCAAUUAAGAAUUACAAUUUCAACAGUCCACAAACAAAAUAAGAUUUUUUUAAUGUAGAGAGAAAUUAAUUAUGUUCAAAGAGCCCUUUUUCUUUCACUCAAUUUCAGUACCCCAAAGCUAAAAACGCAAACAUGACUAUGACAAAUGAAAAUAAGUAUCAUGGGAAUCUGUUUUUUUCCUCUGAGAAAUAAAAUCUAAAUGGAGAUUUGAUACUAUAUGCUAUACUACAUACACUAAGAAUAUUGUAUUUUUCAUAAUUCUGAUUUAAUCUCCUGUAAACUUGAUAUAUUUUAAAAUUUGUAAUUUGUUUUUCAUGAUACUGAAUCUGGUUCCAGUUCUUUUUCAUCAUUUAAUAUACUGGCUACCCGUUCUAAUUAGGAAAACAAGUCCUAGAAAUCUCUUCAUUUUGACAGCAAGUGCUGAUUUGUAAGAAAAUCAUUAAAAAUGCAGCUCUCUAGGAAGCACAUUUUGUUGAUUGUCCUAUUGUCUGAACAUUUUCACAGUGAUUCCUGACUAAAAAUCCUUUUAAUUUUGUAAGCACUACACUAGUGUGUCAUGUCACUAGUAUGUACUUUCAAGCCUUUAAACAGAAAGGAUGGCUCACAGCUAGAUAAUAACUAAGUUUGUUUUCGUUUUGAAAAAGUUUGUAUCUUGCAGAGCAGAAAAGCACUUCUUUUUUUGCUACAUAAGUAUGUGGUAGAAAUGUAUGCUAAGGUAGGCCAGUCAAUCCUUUUUUAUUUAUUUUGUAAAUUUGGUCCCAGAAUAUUUCUGGAAGGAACCACAGGUAGACUAGCUUCCAUUGCAGUCCCUUACCUCACUAACUUCUUUUGUGGCUUUAUCCAGGCACUGUUACUGUUUGUAUGCUAAAGGGUUCAUUUCACUGGGUCUUACUUUCAAAGUUUGUUCCAUUUUGUGUGGUGGCAUGAGCAUUGUGAUCAAGCCAUUAAGUUUGGAAACAACUGAAUGAAAGUCGUCUGUUAUAAUGUAUUUUACUUUAUUUUUAAAUUUCAUUUUAAAUUGACAAUAAUUGUACAUAUUCAUGGGAUACAUAGUGACGUUUCAAUACAUAUCAUGUAUAGUGAUUAUAUCAGGGUAAUCGGCACAUCAUCUCAAACAUUUAUCAUUUCUUUGUGUUGGGAAUUUCAAUAUCUUUUUUUUAGCUGUUUGAGAUUAUGUAAUAUAUUAUUGUUAACUAUAGUCAUCCUACAGUGGUAUAGAAACUACCUAGCUGUAAUGAUGUAUCUUUUAACAAAUCUAAUUUAUUUCUUGACAGUAUAGGGGAAGACUUGAUUACACCCCAUGGCAUUACAGCUAAAAAUUCCAACGUUUUCAGUCUCUUUGUAGCUAUGUUAUCCAGACAUUGAUUUGUAUUUACAUCUCAUCUUCCUUUCUAAGAGAAACAGUGAUGCAGAACCUGAGAGUCAAAUUUAAUAUUCUCUAGGUACCAAGGCAAGGGUUUAUGUUACAGUUUGUGUACUAGUCCAAGUCCCAAGUUGUGACGAUACAGCUCCAUAACCUACCUUUAUACCACCCAGGGAAAGUAUACAGAAGAAAUUCUUGACUUCAUCUAUCCGAAUUUCUACAAGUCAUCUGUUAUUUUUCUGAUAAUCUGCCUGUGUCUCCUGGAAACAUAAGGUGUAGGUUUCUGACACAUAUAUCUAACAUGUAAAGAAGUAACAAUUUCCAAAAUACCUCCAAACAGCGCCACAUCCUAAAGGAAAUUUCUAGGUUUUUCUGCUGAAAUAUCCAUUCCAGCAUUGUGUUUGUUUGCUAGAGCUGCUAUAACAAAGUAUCACAAACUGAGUGCCUUAAAUAAACAAAAGGAAUUUAUUACUUUGUGGUUCAGAAGGCUAGAAGUUGGAGAUCAAGGUGUCAUCACACCAUGGUCCCUCUGAAGGCACCAAGGAUGGAUCUGUUUCAGGACUCCUGGCCUGUAGCAGCAUAACUCCAAUCUUCACAUGAUAUUCUCCCGUUGUAUGUGUUCUUCCCCAAUUUUCCCUUUUUAUAAAGAUAGCAGUCAGAUUAGAUUAGGGCCUAUCCUAAUAAUUUCAUUUUAACCUGACUGUCUUUGUAAAGACCCUAUCUGCAAAUAAAAUCACAUGUAAAGUAUUGGGGCUUAGGACUCCAACAUAUAGAUAUGUUUUAUAUAUAUGGUGAGAUAUAUAUAUAUUUUUUUAUAUAUGGUGAGAUAUAUAUUUAUAUAUGGUGAGAUAUAUAUAUAUAUGGUGAGAUAUAUAUUUAUAUAUAUGGUGAGAUAUAUACAUAUUGUGAUAUAUAUAUAUAUAUAUAUAUAUAUAUAUAUAUAUAUGAAUUUGGUGGAACACAAAAGAACACCUAGCAAGUAUCAUAUGUUCCAAUUUCUUAAAAGUAAAUAAAGGCCUUGUGCCAUUGGUGGUGUUCUGAAA